ACAAUGGAAAAGAUGUCAGAGUGGAAAACAAGCCCAACCAGACAAAGAAGCCCAAGGGGUCCCUGGGGGCACAGACAGUGCCCAAAGCCCUGACAUGACAGCAGAGGGAACAUGGCCUGGGGGGACGGGGGGGGUGGGACACCCGGGUCCUCGGCCUGUGCGGGGACGGCAUCGGGGGACAGUGGGGGUGGGACAGCCCGGAUCUUCAGCCUGUGCGGGGACAUGGCCUGGGGGGACGGCAGGGGUAGGACAGCCCGGGUCCUCGGCCUAUGUGGGGAUGGCCUCGGGGGACAGUGGGGUCAGGACAGCCCGGGUCCUCCAGCCUGUGCAGGGGCUGCACCGUGUUCCGCCCACUCUCCCGCCGCCCUCCGUCAUGUUCAGACCGAUGGCUUCCUUGACACUGUGUCUGCACAGCCAGCAGGCAGCAGGGGCUUGCGGGGCAAAGUCGAGGCAUUUUGAACCCCAGGUUCAAAUGGGGUUCCCAUCUUAAAAUGUUUGAAUGGAACCAGUCGUUUGCCUCCUCCCAGGAAGCUGGCUGAGCUCUGAGUGAUGGUUUAGGAUCAGCAGCAGAGUGGCUGAGGGAUGCUGGGCGCUGGGGACCGAGGCUCUGAGGGCAUUCCUCGCCUCUGGAAUCAGGCCUGGUCUGAGGGUAGGGUGCCCUUUGACACGUGGACUGCUGACCCCAUGGCCCCUGGAGUCCUGGGGACAGAUGGUUCUGAACUGGAUUCUGACCCCAGGGAGAGUUCUGUCCAUAGGAACCAGGACCCCUGGGCACACCCAGACCCUGCUUGGCGUCUGCCCUUCCCCACCCGGCUCUAUCCUUCUCCACAGGGUCUUCCUGUGAGACCACACCAGGACGAGGGGACCCAGCGAGGGCGCCUGAGUGUGGACCACUCGUGUUGCAAAUCACAGGAAAGCUGACGGGCUGGCGAGCAAAGGGAAGAUGAAACCCUGCCCAGAUGGGUCCAGGCUGCCACCGAGGGCCUGAUGUGAGCGUCCUGGCCAUGGGCCCGGUUCCGAUCUGCCUGGAGGCUGCAGCGGCCUGGACCUGGGCAGUCUGAGCUCAGACCUUCCUCCCGUGGCCACUGCGGGGAUCAUGAGGGCAGGCCCAGCCCAAAGCACAGGAGUCCUUGGACCGGGGGGCAGCUGACCCCUGGAGCCCCCAGGCUAGGACCUCUGCUAAUCUCUUCCCUGGUGUGUGGCGAGUCCUCGCUCAGGCCUACGGCCGUGAGCAAGGCCCUGCUGGGCGUGAGGUCCCUUCCAAGUGGGGAGGUCUCUCGCCUUGCCCCAGACGGGACAGACUCAGAGCUGCCACCUCUGUAGCCGUCUCCCGCCCCACUGCCUGCAGAGGCCCCAUACUCACAGCUGUCCUCUUCCUCCGUAAACACGCUGACCACCUGGCAGCCACAGACAAAGCCCAGAAGCUGAAAGACACCACAGGCAGGGGCGUGAGUGCGGCCAGGCGAGCCUGUGGGGUGUCAUUGAGGCGAUGUGGGCCGAAGCACUGGAGCGCCCCUGACCACCAAGGCCCUGCCUCUCCUGGACCUCAGGUUCCUCCUCUGUGACUUGGAGUGGGAGAGCUGACCCGUGGGUAUCCUCAGCUCUCAAGCUCCGGACGCACCCCUGCCUUCCACCCCACCCCACUCAACUGGGUAGGGGGCAGGUGGGUGAGGAUAAUGGAUAUUGGGUGGGGAAGAUGAGCAGGUCAGCCUGAGUGGCUGCAGGGAGCGGGGUGAGGACACAGAAGCCCAGGCUGGAUGAACCCCAGGCCAGCACAGUCCCAGCCCUGCGUCCCCUCGGGCCUCUUGCCUUUGGCCCCAGCCCACUCCAGCCAGCAGCCACCAGGGGUUCCUCCUCCUCUGUGGAGCAAGCCAUCUGGGAUUCUGGUUUUGAGCCCGGCAAAGUGCAGGAGAGACAGGCUGAGGACUCGGGGUCCAGCGGGCAACUCCGGGCAGAGUUGGGGGCUGGCUGCUGCCUUUGGGGCAGGGGUCAGGCAGGGAGAGGGGAGGGACUGGGAGUCCAGGGCAGAGGGCAGGCCGCUGCAAAGCCCCACACACCUCGCAGACACCUGCAUCCAGGGCCACUGAGGGAAAAAGGGCUCUGGCAAAGGGGGGGCAGUGCUGCCGCAGCCAGAAACACCAACAGCAUGAGCGAGAGGGCCUGGCCAGGGGCACUCCAGGCCACAGACACCGAGGGAGGCGGCAGUGGGUCUGUGACUGGAGGGACCCCGGAACGAGGCAGGAAACCUUCCUGGUUGCACCUCAGGCCAACCACUCAGCAGCCGGGUGACCCCAAAAAUUCACUUCAUCUUCUGGUCUUGGUUUCUUCCUCCAUAGACUUGGCCCAACAGCCCCCCGUGAAGGCCACCGUGCCCAGGAGAGGAGACAGGACACGCAGGCCAGGCCCCAGGGCUGGACAUGCUUGGGCUCCGUCCCCCCGACCCCCGACCCCAUCUGGUACAGGCAAGUUGGUGGUUGCUUUCCUGGAAAUCCAGCUCCUUUCUAGGGGUCAGUCAGGGGCCAGGAGACCUCUCUUACCACCAAGCAGGCAGACCUAUCUCCUUGAUAUUGAGACAAGCUCAAGAAGCUGUCCCAAAUGGCCAUUUCUGGUUCCAUGCCACGGCCAGGGUGGGAGCAGCGGUGAGGGUGGGCAACCUCCACGGCUCGUCCCCCUCCUCACCCCAAAGGAGCCCAAGACGCCCCCAUCCCGGAGCUGGCCGUGGCGCCGAACAGGCAGCCGAGCUUGGGGAGCCAUUGGAAGAUGCCCCUUCCAGCCGGUGCCCUCCUGCCUGGGGACCUGCAGGCCACCUCUGUCCCACACCCCCAUGCUCCCCGCCCUGCACACCACCGCCUCCUGCCCAUCCUCCUGGCUCCAGCCCCAGGUCCACCCCAAAGCUCUCCCCUCUCCCUGCUGCAUGGAGGCCUGGGAUCUGCAGGCCCCGCACCCCAACCCCCAGAGCCUGGCCUUGUCAGACGACUCUCUUGCCACCACCAUUUCCAUCCCCAGCACAGCUGGGCAGAGGCCAACCAAGCCGCCAGCCUCUCCCAGACCCUCCAAAGCAAACAGCAGGGGCGAGAUCCUAGCGAGGACUAGCUGGCUGGAAUUUAGAAACUACAUCCUAUCAAAGAAAUUCCCAUCCCUGGGAGUCAGGAUAAAAGCCAACAGGAGGCCCCAUCUCCCCAACCAUGCAGAGUGCCCACUCCUCCAGCCUCGGCUCCCAUAGCACGCCAGCCCCCUCCGAGAGACUCUUCAUUCAUUCCCCUCAAGCUUCCUUUUUUUUUUUUUGAGACAGAGUCUCGCUCUGUCACCCAGGCUGGAGUGCAGUGGCGUGAUCUCUGCUCACUGCAAGCUCUGCCUCCCGGGUUCAUGCCAUUCUCCUGCUUCAGCCUCCCGAGGAGCUGGGACUACAGGCGCCCGCCACCACGCCCGGCUAAUUGUUUUGUAUUUUUAGUAGAGACAGGGUUUCACCGUGUUAGCCAGGAUGGUCUCAGUCUCCUGACCUCGUGAUCCGCCUGCCUCGGCCUCCCAAAGUGCUGGGAUUACAGGUGUGAGCCACCGCACCCAGCCUAGCUUCUUUUCUGUUGCCUCCUCACAAAGCCUAAUCUCAGGAGCUUUGAUGUGCACACUUGGGAAAUUGGCUCUUUCUCCUCCAGUGGCAGGCACCUGGGUUCCACACAUUUUGGGGGCAAUUGGGGCCCCCUCUGUGCCUUGCUGACUGGCUUUGGUGGGAGAAACAGGCCCCGACUGGAGCUGGCAGGGUGCGUCUGUGGCCCCUUGCUAUGGGGCAGCACCUUCCUGGCCUGAUUUCCUGCAGGACCAGAGCAGAGCCCAGGAAGGAGCCCCGGGAGCUCACGAGGCCACCCGCACCGUCACGUGUGCUCAGGCCACGGGCUCCUUAGAUUUGGAAUUCAGCUCCCACCGCCAGCCGCCGGCCAUGGAGCCUCGCUCCUGGAAGCCCCAGGUCCACCUGGUGUGUUGCGUCGACACCACCGUGCGCACCAGGAAAAGCCAGGGAGCCUCGAGAUCGGUCAGAAGUUCCUCCAGCGACGGCACCAGCCGUGCUGCAGUCACAUUGGCCCUGCCCCCGGAGCUCUUGAGAGGCGGGAGCUGAGGCACACGGAGGUUGUUAGGCUCACAGAGGCGGCACAGCGGGGAAGUGGCCGUGUGGCCAUACCAGGAGCAGCAUCGUAGCCCCUGUUCUCUACCAACCCGUGCAGGGCCGGAGAGGACGGCAGAGUCCCGUUCCCGCACAAGCAACAGCUGCUCCUCAGCGCCACCCGGGGCCACAGAAUCCCUGUCCGGUCAGACCUGGGUCACGUGGCGCCAGCCUUGCCAGAUGCAUACGCCAGGGUUCCCGACAAGGCUGAGGGGCUUCUUGCCAGCCCAGCCUCAGGCUCUGUCCACUUCCUGUGACCGGCAUGGGCUCGGGGCAGCCGAGGGAACAGGCGGGACACGCAUGGAUGGGUUUGUCAGGAAGAUGCAUGCCCCUCCUCCUUGGGGCCGUCAAAGCCAGAGGCGGGGUGUCUCGGCCUGAUCCGAUUCCUUCCCACUCCCCACAGCAAACACCACGCUCAACUUGAGAAAGCGCCUGGGUUGGCCCCGCCUGGGGGAGGUGGUUUGCAGAGGAGGCACUGAGGUGCCAGCCACAUGGGACCCACCCGUGAUACCUUAACCUCUCCAGCAAGGGUGGGGGAUGAGGAAGGCAGAGACACGCCUGAGGCCAGGUCAGCUGGCCCCGCCUCAGGGAGAUGAGCCCCCAGCUCCAUGUCCCCUCCCCCAUCAACCCAUCCCCACCCGGGGGCCCCCUUCCCCACGCUCACCGCGAUCAGGAUCUGCAGGCAACUGUGUAGGGCCUCCACAUAGCUGGGCUCCAGGGCACAGCCAGCACCUGACACCAGGGCCUGGCCAUGGGGGGCCCCGAGGCCCACUGCUGGCACCUCCUCAUGCAGACAGCCUGGCCAGCGCUCACGCCACCAGGAGCGAUGCCGGGAGAGGCUGAAGGUCAGUAGCUCGCUGUCCUAGGGGAGAGGUGCAGGAGCAGGGCCGGUUAGCACCAGGAGGUGGGCGGCCUCACCCACUGCAGCCUGCGGGGACGCCACCACACCGAGGCAAGGGGAGGUCCUGUCCUCUCACCUCCCCUGUCCUCCCACUGCACCCCGCCCCCAGGGCUCCAGCCAUGGUGGGGAAAGGAAUACCAAGGCCCUCCCAGCCGCUCCUGCGCCUGCCCUCGACCCACACACCUCCUCCUCCAGGAAGGCCUCCCUGCCCAGACCCCAGAACUCGCUCUCAGGGGCACCGGGCCCCUUCCUCGUGUCGCUGGCCAAAGCUGCCAUGUGACGUGUGUCUGCCUCGGGACAGUCUUCCCGGCUGCAGCCCCAGGUGUGGUUCCAGGAAGCGGGGGCCCGUCUGCCUGGCUGGGCACCUGCCCCAGUGCCCACCUGUGCUACACUGGCCAGAGCAGAGAGCCCCUGGGGGAGACCAAAAUCCAUCCACCCUGGCUUUAGGACCACCCUCUGAGCUGUAAGCAAAGUGCCUGAAACAGCCUCGGUCAGGGUGGGCUCAGCAAUGGCCCCCACCCUGUUUCCCCUGAACAGCCUCGGUCAGGGUCGGCUCAGCGAUGGCCUUUUCCCACCCCCUCCCCCCACGUUUCCCCUGGUUCCCUGCAUUGCAGGAGGCACGAGGCUUUACCAGCCUGGAGGGUUGGUCGGGCUGGGACAAAGGACCCCACGUGGCCCCAGGAGGGUGGUGUCCAUUCACCUGCAGAUCUCUGCCAGGGUUUGCCCCUGCUCUGAGGCCCCUCUUCCCCAGCUGGAGCCCCCUCGCCUGCCAAUACCCACAGACGCCUUUCUUUCACCAAUCAAAUCACUGGUCUUUCCCCAAACCUUUACUGAGUUACCAACUACAGACCAGGGCUGUUCUGGGUGCUGGGGACAGAGCCAUGCACAGACUGAGCCCCUGCCUCAGACGACAGAUGAAAAGCAAACACAGGGGGUGUUACCAGGGGCCCGGCCCAGACCCCAGGGAAGGACCUCGCGCUGCCUCCCAGUCUGCACUCACCUUUAAGAGGCCACCGACUUCCAGGUAGAAGCAGAUGAUGAAGACGUUCCAGGUGACCCAGACGGCUGCCCACAGCGUGUACUAGGGAGAGGAGAGGAUGGGGCGGCAGCUGAACACAGCUCCCGGGCACACCUGCUUGCAUCCAGCCCCCGGGGGAAGGGGUCCCAUGAUCGCAUAGGAGGGGCGGCCUCUGCUCCUGAGUCUGGCGGCCCCCAGAUGCACAGCAUGGAGAAAGGGGUCCCCCAAGCCCACCCUGGGACACGUCUCAGAGCUUUCCCACGUGGGUGCCCCGGGAAUGAGGCGGUGGGACAGCCAGCUCAAGGGAGCCCCAGCGCAGGUCGGCGUACGGACACAGCAUCCCUGGCUGAGCUGCCGUGACCUGUCCUCGCCUCACCGGGCUGACAUUACACGUGGACAGCACAGGCCUCCACUGCAGAGCACCCCAGAAGCCACCCCCAAGAGAGCACCCCAAAGAGCUGCCAGCUGCUUUUGUAAAUAAAGUUUUGCGGACACAGCCACA